GUUUGUUUACUUGGCGAGACUUGGAGCUGAGGUCAUUUGGAGCUGUUUAAUACUGAAGAGCUGUUGAGCACUGGAAAGUGCUGUGUAACCCUGGAAAAGAACCGUGUAACGCUGCAGAAGUGUGUGGUAGCUAUGCCGGAGGUGUCAUCUAAAGGUGCUACCAUUUCCAAGAAGGGCUUUAAGAAAGCUGUCGUUAAGACCCAGAAAAAGGAAGGCAAAAAGCGCAAGAGGACCCGUAAGGAGAGUUAUUCUAUUUACAUCUACAAAGUGCUAAAGCAGGUCCAUCCGGACACUGGCAUCUCUUCGAAAGCUAUGAGCAUUAUGAAUUCCUUCGUCACUGAUAUCUUUGAGCGUAUAGCGAGCGAGGCAUCACGUUUGGCUCACUACAGCAAGCGCUCCACCAUUUCUUCCAGAGAGAUUCAGACAGCAGUGCGCUUGCUACUGCCGGGAGAGCUGGCUAAACAUGCUGUGUCUGAGGGCACCAAGGCUGUCACUAAGUACACCAGCUCCAAGUAAGCCUGCUAAGUAAACGUCAUUUCUAACCCAAAGGCUCUUUUCAGAGCCACUUA